GGCAUUGCCUCACAGACCUUCCUCAGAGCCGCUUUCAGAAAAGCAAGCUGCUUCUGGUUGGGCCCAGACCUGCCUUGAGGAGCCUGUAGAGUUAAAAAAUGAACCCCACGGAUAUAGCAGACACCACCCUCGAUGAAAGCAUAUACAGCAAUUACUAUCUGUAUGAAAGUAUCCCCAAGCCUUGCACCAAAGAAGGCAUCAAGGCAUUUGGGGAGCUCUUCCUGCCCCCACUGUAUUCCUUGGUUUUUGUAUUUGGUCUGCUUGGAAAUUCUGUGGUGGUUCUGGUCCUGUUCAAAUACAAGCGGCUCAGGUCCAUGACUGAUGUGUACCUGCUCAACCUUGCCAUCUCGGAUCUGCUCUUCGUGUUUUCCCUCCCUUUUUGGGGCUACUAUGCAGCAGACCAGUGGGUUUUUGGGCUAGGUCUGUGCAAGAUGAUUUCCUGGAUGUACUUGGUGGGCUUUUACAGUGGCAUAUUCUUUGUCAUGCUCAUGAGCAUUGAUAGAUACCUGGCAAUUGUGCACGCGGUGUUUUCCUUGAGGGCAAGGACCUUGACUUAUGGGGUCAUCACCAGUUUGGCUACAUGGUCAGUGGCUGUGUUCGCCUCCCUUCCUGGCUUUCUGUUCAGCACUUGUUAUACUGAGCGCAACCAUACCUACUGCAAAACCAAGUACUCUCUCAACUCCACGACGUGGAAGGUUCUCAGCUCCCUGGAAAUCAACAUUCUCGGAUUGGUGAUCCCCUUAGGGAUCAUGCUGUUUUGCUACUCCAUGAUCAUCAGGACCUUGCAGCAUUGUAAAAAUGAGAAGAAGAACAAGGCGGUGAAGAUGAUCUUUGCCGUGGUGGUCCUCUUCCUUGGGUUCUGGACACCUUACAACAUAGUGCUCUUCCUAGAGACCCUGGUGGAGCUAGAAGUCCUUCAGGACUGCACCUUUGAAAGAUACUUGGACUAUGCCAUCCAGGCCACAGAAACUCUGGCUUUUGUUCACUGCUGCCUUAAUCCCAUCAUCUACUUUUUUCUGGGGGAGAAAUUUCGCAAGUACAUCCUACAGCUCUUCAAAACCUGCAGGGGCCUUUUUGUGCUCUGCCAAUACUGUGGGCUCCUCCAAAUUUACUCUGCUGACACCCCCAGCUCAUCUUACACGCAGUCCACCAUGGAUCAUGAUCUCCAUGAUGCUCUGUAGAAAAAUGAAAUGGUGAAAUGCAGAGUCAAUGAACUUUCCACAUUCAGAGCUUACUUAAAAUUGUAUUUUAGUAAGAGAUUCCUGAGCCAGUGUCAGGAGGAAGGCUUACACCCACAGUGGAAAGACAGCUUCUCAUCCUGCAGGCAGCUUUUUCUCUCCCACUAGACAAGUCCAGCCUGGCAAGGGUUCACCUGGGCUGAGGCAUCCUUCCUCACACCAGGCUUGCCUGCAGGCAUGAGUCAGUCUGAUGAGAACUCUGAGCAGUGCUUGAAUGAAGUUGUAGGUAAUAUUGCAAGGCAAAGACUAUUCCCUUCUAACCUGAACUGAUGGGUUUCUCCAGAGGGAAUUGCAGAGUACUGGCUGAUGGAGUAAAUCGCUACCUUUUGCUGUGGCAAAUGGGCCCUCUAAUUAAUUUCUUGCUUUUGCGGAACAAUAUAGAUAACUGUUUUUCUAAUAACAUAUCUCAGGCAAAGUAUAUUCCAUUGAGCCAGAUGUAUGAAGAAACAAUUAGCGAAGUGAUGAAACCAGAUCUCAAUUAUUUAUUGUAAAGGAUUAUCUGUUAAUUGAAACCAAACUUUUUAUACUGAUAUAAGGGUAAGGAUAUGAAGACAUUAGCCAAGGUCUGCUUUCCAAACGUGAACUACAAGGCAUUCAAAAUCCAAACAUAUUUAUGAAAAUUCAAACACAGUUUCUCACUUGUUUGUGGACAUGUUUUGUUCUAAUUUUAACAGAGGAAUAUUAAAAAAUUUUAAAUAGGCUGGGCACGGUGGCCUGUAAUCCCAGCACUGUGGGAGGCCAAGGUGGGCGGAUCACCUGAGGUCAGGAGUUCGAGACCAGCCUGGCCAACAUGGAGAAACCCUGUCUCUACUAAAAAAUACAAAAUUAGCCAGGUGUGGUGGCGCAUGCCUGUAAUCCCAGCUACUCAGGAGGCUGAGGCUGGAGAAUAACUUGAAUCCGGGAGGUGGAGGUUGCGGUGAGCCGAGAUCGCGCCAUUGUACUCCAACCUGGGCAAAAAGAGCGAAACUCUGUCUCAAAAAAAAAAAAAAAAAAUUAAAUAAUACAUAGGCCAAGAAUACAUUUAUUUGAGGUCAUUUACUUGUUUUUUUUUUUUUUUUUUUUUUUGAGAUGGAAUCUUGCUCUGUCACCCAGUCUGGAGUGCAGUGGCGCGAUCUCGGCUCACUGCAAGCUCUGCCUCACGGGUUCGCACCAUUCUCCUGCCUCAGCCUCCCAAGUAGGUGGGACUACAGGCACCUGCCCCCAUGCCUGGCUAAUUUUUUGUAUUUUCAGUAGAGAUGGGGUUUCACCAUGUUAGCAAGGAUGGUUUUAAUCUCCUGACCUCGUGAUCCACCCGCCUCGGCCUCCCAAAGUGCUGGGAUUACAGGUGUGAGCCAUCACGCCCGGCCACUUGUUUAUUUUUUAUUUUAUUUUAUUUUAUUUUUGAGAUGGAGUCUCACUCUGUCACCCAAGCUGGAGUGCAGUGGCACUCGGUUCACUGCAAAGUCUGCCUCCCAGGUUCAAGCGAUUCUCCUGCCUCAGCUUCUCAAGCAGCUGGGAUUAGAGGUGUGCACCACUACGCCAGGCUAAUUUUUGUAUUUUUAGUAGAGAUGGGGUUUCACCAUAUUGGCCAGGCUAGUCUUGAACUCCUGACCUCAGGUGAUCUGCCUGCUUCAGCCUCCCAAAGUGCUGGGAUUACAGGCGUGAGCCACCUCGCCCAGCCAAGGUCUUUUACUUGUUUAUAAACAGUCUCUUCAUAAUUAAAAUUAAGGAUUAAUAAAGUAUGACAAUACCUCCUUAAUCAUUUUGAAGUGCCUGCUAUCAAUUGAAAUAAAAACAAUCAACUAAAA